AGUAGAGGGGGCUCCGGGGCUGAGUCCGCGUCGACGCCGGCCGCGGAGGCGGCACCAUGGGCAAGGGGUAGAGGGGCAAGUUGGCCACCGCCGCCGCCGGGGGUGGUGGGAGAGCCGCUCCGGGGGCGGGGGCCGGUGGGGGAGGGAGGGGCGGGCAGCCGCGCCGCCGCGGCACUUUUUUAAUUUUUUCGGGUGCCGCAGCGGCGACCCCUCGGCGCCGAUGUCCCUGAUCCCUGGAGCGACGACGGCCGCUGCCUAAGCUGGAAAGGGUGAGAGAUUUUUGGUGAUCAUUCAAUUCUGCCUCUGCUAACCAGGCACAGCUUUCUGCAGCACAGCUGAUGGUGGUGACAGCACAGCCUGUGGCCACAGAAGAGAACAGAACUCCUGUGCUCACCUAAGGAUUAAGCCCACGGGGCUGGUGCAUUAGCUCAGUGCUCCUGGAUUCAAAACAGUUGUAGAAUAUGUUCAGGAAGAACGGUAAAAUACCCUCCAAUGAGAGAGCCUGCGGUAGGGGUGCCUUCAGUGGUCCAAAAUGGCAGUUACUUCAGAUUCUCCACAAUCUGAGCAGUUUAUUAUACUAUGGUGGUAAGGGGAAAGGCUUGGUGAAGAUUAAUGUUAAAUACAUAAGAUAAAAUGACCCACUGAUUUUUUUUAAUUAAAAAAUGGGCCCCUUUCAUAUCAAAACUGAAGAUGGAUACAUUACCUGAGGGUGCACAUCAGCCAACAAAAGUGGGUUCAGCAUCCCCCCAACCCUGAACCCAGAGCAGUCCCAACAGCCUGCCCCAUGUAGUACCUGUUAGUGAAGUACCACCUUUGACCCACCUUGCUCAGUUUCCUCACUUGUUCUUAAGAGAAAUUAGUUCCUUGUGACCCAGUUGUGUUUCCAGCUAUAGAGAAACUGUAACACCACUGGGUUUUAGCUGGAUAACAUUUUUAACACAUGUCUGCAUUUGAGUUAGAAUAGCAGAGAUCAGAGUACUGAUAAUCCUGAAGGAUAAUUGGGCCUGUGUCCACUGGCCUGGAGGAACACAUAUUUGUGUGAGUGGCCAAGCAGAGCACCACUGACCCCUCCUGCCAUUGGAAAGCACAGUGGCCUUGCUUCAAUGGCAGCGUGUUCUAAGUCAUGCCAUUUUACUUAGUCUUCAUUCACUCGGUUAGAAAUGAGGUCAAUUAUUCCUGAAAAAAAAAUUGGUAAUACUUGGACUAAAUAAAAAACUGCACCUGCCCAUAGAUUUGUCUUAGACUUCUUGAAUAAAAUGAAUGAUGUUGGGACAUACAGAAUAUAGACAGAGUUUAGAGAACAGGAUGCAUGAAUUAAACAAAGUCUCACCUCUCCAGACUUGUAUUUGCAACUUCUGAUUCUGUUAUGCACAACAGCAUGUAUCAGAAAGUGAGAUAAUUUCCCAGAAAUGUUAGAAAGUUUUAAUUAGUGUACUGAUGCUAGAGAAAGCAGCCAUGAAAGUCAUCCUCAAUACAAAGUUGCUGGCACUUUUAUGGACAGUAUAUAAGGAGGAAUGCCAGCUCCUGAGCAGGCCUCAUUGGUGGAGGAGGGGCAACCACAGACCCGCCAGGAAGCUGCCUCCACUGGCCCAGGCAUGGAACCCGAGACCACAGCCACCACUAUUCUAGCAUCCGUGAAGGAGCAGGAGCUUCAGUUUCAGCGACUCACCCGAGAACUGGAAGUGGAAAGGCAGAUUGUUGCCAGUCAGCUAGAAAGAUGUAGGCUUGGAGCAGAAUCACCAAGCAUCGCCAGCACCAGCUCAACUGAGAAGUCAUUUCCUUGGAGAUCAACAGACGUGCCAAAUACUGGUGUAAGCAAACCUAGAGUUUCUGACGCUGUCCAGCCCAACAACUAUCUCAUCAGGACAGAGCCAGAACAAGGAACCCUCUAUUCACCAGAACAGACAUCUCUCCAUGAAAGUGAGGGAUCAUUGGGUAACUCAAGAAGUUCAACACAAAUGAAUUCUUAUUCCGACAGUGGAUACCAGGAAGCAGGGAGUUUCCACAACAGCCAGAACGUGAGCAAGGCAGACAACAGACAGCAGCAUUCAUUCAUAGGAUCAACUAACAACCAUGUGGUGAGGAAUUCAAGAGCUGAAGGACAAACACUGGUUCAGCCAUCAGUAGCCAAUCGGGCCAUGAGAAGAGUUAGUUCAGUUCCAUCUAGAGCACAGUCUCCUUCUUAUGUUAUCAGCACAGGCGUGUCUCCUUCAAGGGGGUCUCUGAGAACUUCUCUGGGUAGUGGAUUUGGCUCUCCGUCAGUGACCGACCCCCGACCUCUGAACCCCAGUGCAUAUUCCUCCACCACAUUACCUGCUGCACGGGCAGCCUCUCCGUACUCACAGAGACCCGCCUCCCCAACAGCUAUACGGCGGAUUGGGUCAGUCACCUCCCGGCAGACCUCCAAUCCCAACGGACCAACCCCUCAAUACCAAACCACCGCCAGAGUGGGGUCCCCACUGACCCUGACGGAUGCACAGACUCGAGUAGCUUCCCCAUCCCAAGGCCAGGUGGGGUCGUCGUCCCCCAAACGCUCAGGGAUGACCGCCGUACCACAGCAUCUGGGACCUUCACUGCAAAGGACUGUUCAUGACAUGGAGCAAUUCGGACAGCAGCAGUAUGACAUUUAUGAGAGGAUGGUUCCACCCAGGCCAGACAGCCUGACAGGCUUACGGAGUUCCUAUGCUAGUCAGCAUAGUCAGCUUGGGCAAGACCUUCGUUCUGCCGUGUCUCCCGACUUGCACAUUACUCCUAUAUAUGAGGGGAGGACCUAUUACAGCCCAGUGUACCGCAGCCCAAACCAUGGAACUGUGGAGCUCCAAGGAUCGCAGACGGCGUUGUAUCGCACAGGUUCAGGUAUUGGAAAUCUACAAAGGACAUCCAGCCAACGAAGUACCCUUACAUACCAAAGAAAUAAUUAUGCUCUGAACACAACAGCUACCUACGCGGAGCCCUACAGGCCUAUACAAUACCGAGUGCAAGAGUGCAAUUAUAACAGGCUUCAGCAUGCAGUGCCGGCUGAUGAUGGCACCACAAGAUCCCCAUCAAUAGACAGCAUUCAGAAGGACCCCAGGGAGUUUGCCUGGCGUGAUCCUGAGUUGCCUGAGGUCAUUCACAUGCUUCAGCACCAGUUCCCAUCUGUUCAGGCAAAUGCAGCGGCCUACCUGCAGCACCUGUGCUUUGGUGACAACAAAGUGAAGAUGGAGGUGUGUAGGUUAGGGGGAAUCAAGCAUCUGGUUGACCUUCUGGACCACAGAGUUUUGGAAGUUCAGAAGAAUGCUUGUGGUGCCCUUCGAAACCUCGUUUUUGGCAAGUCUACAGAUGAAAAUAAAAUAGCAAUGAAGAAUGUUGGUGGGAUACCUGCCUUGUUGCGACUGUUGAGAAAAUCUAUUGAUGCAGAAGUAAGGGAGCUUGUUACAGGAGUUCUUUGGAAUUUAUCCUCAUGUGAUGCUGUAAAAAUGACAAUCAUUCGAGAUGCUCUCUCAACCUUAACAAACACUGUGAUUGUUCCACAUUCUGGAUGGAAUAACUCUUCUUUUGAUGAUGAUCAUAAAAUUAAAUUUCAGACUUCACUAGUUCUGCGUAACACGACAGGUUGCCUAAGGAACCUCAGCUCCGCGGGGGAAGAAGCUCGGAAGCAAAUGCGGUCCUGCGAGGGGCUGGUAGACUCACUGUUGUAUGUGAUCCACACGUGUGUGAACACAUCCGAUUACGACAGCAAGACGGUGGAGAACUGCGUGUGCACCCUGAGGAACCUGUCCUAUCGGCUGGAGCUGGAGGUGCCCCAGGCCCGGUUACUGGGACUGAACGAAUUGGAUGACUUACUAGGAAAAGAGUCUCCCAGCAAAGACUCUGAGCCAAGUUGCUGGGGGAAGAAGAAGAAAAAGAAAAAGAGGACUCCGCAAGAAGAUCAAUGGGAUGGAGUUGGUCCUAUCCCAGGACUGUCGAAGUCCCCCAAAGGGGUUGAGAUGCUGUGGCACCCAUCGGUGGUAAAACCAUAUCUGACUCUUCUAGCAGAAAGUUCCAACCCAGCCACCUUGGAAGGCUCUGCAGGGUCUCUCCAGAACCUCUCUGCUGGCAACUGGAAGUUUGCAGCAUAUAUCCGGGCGGCCGUCCGAAAAGAAAAGGGGCUCCCCAUCCUUGUGGAGCUUCUGAGAAUGGAUAACGAUAGAGUUGUUUCUUCCGUGGCAACAGCCUUGAGGAAUAUGGCACUAGAUGUUCGCAACAAGGAGCUCAUAGGCAAAUACGCCAUGCGAGACCUGGUCAACCGGCUCCCCGGCGGCAAUGGCCCCAGUGUCUUGUCUGAUGAGACCAUGGCAGCCAUCUGCUGUGCUCUGCACGAGGUCACCAGCAAAAACAUGGAGAACGCAAAAGCCCUGGCCGACUCAGGAGGCAUAGAGAAGCUGGUGAACAUAACCAAAGGCAGGGGCGACAGAUCAUCUCUGAAAGUGGUGAAGGCAGCAGCCCAGGUCUUGAAUACAUUAUGGCAAUAUCGGGACCUCCGGAGCAUUUAUAAAAAGGAUGGGUGGAAUCAGAACCAUUUUAUUACACCUGUGUCGACAUUGGAGCGAGACCGAUUCAAAUCACAUCCUUCCUUGUCUACCACCAACCAACAGAUGUCACCCAUCAUUCAGUCAGUCGGCAGCACCUCUUCCUCACCAGCACUGUUAGGAAUCAGAGACCCUCGCUCUGAAUACGAUAGGACCCAGCCACCUAUGCAGUAUUACAAUAGCCAAGGGGAUGCCACACAUAAAGGCCUGUACCCUGGCUCCAGCAAACCUUCACCAAUUUACAUCAGUUCCUAUUCCUCACCAGCAAGAGAACAAAAUAGACGGCUACAGCAUCAACAGCUGUAUUAUAGUCAAGAUGACUCCAACAGAAAGAACUUUGAUGCAUACAGAUUGUAUUUGCAGUCUCCUCAUAGCUAUGAAGAUCCUUAUUUUGAUGACCGAGUUCACUUUCCAGCUUCUACUGAUUACUCAACACAGUAUGGACUGAAAUCGACCACAAAUUAUGUAGACUUUUAUUCCACUAAACGACCUUCUUAUAGAGCAGAACAGUACCCAGGGUCCCCAGACUCAUGGGUGUAGCAUCAAGAUGCCCAACAGAGGAACUCUUUCUUUCUAACCUUGUUCAGAUUGAGGUGAAAAGUCCAUCUUGCUGAUUUGAUGAUUGAAAUGUGAAAGUGAAGUGGAAGGAAUGAAUGAAGUGUGUUUUUUUUUUCUUUUUUGAGGAAUUAUCAGGGAAGUGAGGAAAUGUUUGGGAGAGGACUUUCUAAGCUCUAUUUAGGUGUUAGAUCUAAUUACUUAUAGAUUCUGUAGUCUGGUGAAGGUGUGGGUGACGUGAUGAGAGGUUUGAGAAAUGGGUGAAAUGAAAUGGGGGAUAUGUAGGUCAAAUCAAAUUAAAGAUGAUUUUUUUAAUGUGAAUAAAGUUAUGUUCUGAUAGUUUGUACAGAAAAAAUAAAAUGGAUGCCCAUGUUUUAUUGCUAUUACUAAAUGUCAAGAUUGUAUGCUAUUAUGUCUUGUAAAUUUCUUUUGUUGGUGUAAAUAUGGAAAUGCCACAUUGGUUAAGUGCCAUCAUUUGUAAUGCAAUGUGUCACUUGAAAAGAGAUUUGAAGAAACUGACAACUUCAAAAACAAAUGAGAAGCCCAAGGAACUGUGAGCAAUUAAAAGCAAACCGCGACACCCUUUGUCUCCACCACACAUAGUGUACUUUGGAAGCACAACGUCCAGGCUGGUACCGCAGCGCCAUGCCCAUUCCUCGCCUCAUUCAUAGGACACUUCACUGCCAUUUUCUAUUCACAUAAAAGAAAAAUAAAUGUGGAAAUUUCAUCCUUGGAAA